GCAGUCACCGCGGACGCCAAUCUUGUGCAUGGAGUCGCCAUUUUGCUCCUAGAGAGGCCGCCAGGAGACCCGGCGCUUUCUUCCUUCUGCAGCUGAGGCUGCGGCGGGGCCGGGGCUGGGGUCGGGGCCAGAAUUCAGCGGGGUGCCAAGUCGUUUUCUGUGUGGGUUGAGAGACAGGCUGUGCAGCCCACUGUUGCAUAGGACUAACUACUACAAAUCAUGCUGAGACCGAGCUAUUUUUGCUGCUUAGAGGCUUUGCAGCCUUGAGAGGAAUUUUGUUGUCAGAGAAUAAAAGGAGGUUGUCCAUAAUUGACUUUAAGCAGCAAUCAGUAAAACAUUGAGCUCUUCAGCUCCGCCUUUCUUGCUCUGAAAAUUGGAAAACCAAGAAGGUUUUGAUGUUUUGUGUGACGCCACCUGAAUUAGAAACCAAGAUGAACAUAACCAAAGGUGGUCUGGUGUUGUUUUCAGCAAACUCGAAUUCAUCAUGUAUGGAGCUAUCAAAGAAAAUUGCAGAAAACAAGAGUACAAAUUCAAGAGUCUGUGAGGGGAAAAGAUGUUUUCAUCAUCCAAACUGUUUCGAAGGACGUGAACACCACCAUCAUGGAGCUCCUGAUCAUGGUGUAUGCAUGUAAGACCUCUUGUGCCAAGAGCAUCAUUGGCGUGAUACCCUACUUUCCUUACAGCAAGCAGUGCAAGAUGAGAAAAAGAGGCUCCAUUGUCUCUAAAUUGCUGGCUUCCAUGAUGUGCAAAGCUGGUCUAACUCAUCUUAUUACUAUGGAUUUACACCAGAAGGAAAUUCAGGGCUUCUUCAAUAUUCCUGUUGACAAUUUAAGAGCAUCUCCCUUCUUAUUACAGUAUAUUCAAGAAGAGAUCCCAGAUUACAGGAAUGCAGUAAUCGUGGCCAAGUCUCCAGCCUCGGCGAAGAGGGCACAGUCUUUUGCUGAGCGCCUGCGCCUGGGAAUUGCAGUGAUUCAUGGAGAGGCGCAGGAUGCCGAGUCGGACUUGGUGGAUGGACGGCAUUCCCCACCCAUGGUCAGAAGUGUGGCUGCCAUCCACCCCAGCCUGGAGAUCCCCAUGCUGAUUCCUAAAGAAAAGCCCCCAAUCACGGUUGUGGGUGAUGUUGGAGGAAGGAUUGCCAUCAUCGUGGAUGACAUCAUUGAUGAUGUUGACAGCUUUCUUGCUGCAGCAGAGACCCUGAAGGAAAGAGGUGCAUAUAAGAUCUUUGUGAUGGCAACUCAUGGCUUGUUGUCUUCUGACGCCCCCCGGCGGAUUGAAGAGUCUGCCAUUGAUGAGGUGGUGGUCACCAAUACAAUUCCACAUGAAGUCCAGAAGCUCCAGUGCCCCAAGAUUAAAACUGUGGAUAUCAGCAUGAUCCUUUCAGAGGCGAUCCGUCGGAUCCACAAUGGGGAGUCCAUGUCCUACCUUUUCAGAAACAUAGGCUUAGAUGACUGAGUUUUCCUUUAGGAAAACUCCCGAGGGCCAAACUGGAAACAUAAGAGUGACUGCUCGGUGGGAUGGAUUUCACAGGAACCGUCAUGCUUGUUCCUCCCUCUCCCCUGUAACCUCACUUCUUAUUGAUUCCUAAGAAGAUAGACCAACUUUUUAUGUCGGUUUGGGUGUUUGUGAGUUUGGGGAGCAAUUUUUAUAAAAGAAAAACUUUAUUCUCCUCUUUUGAAAAGGUAAGACCUCGUUUUAGUUGUAACUGUUUAAAAAAUAACACUUGGAAUAAGAUUUGUAAGCUCACAAAGCCUUCUUCCAAAGUUGCUUGAGCCAAGUGCUUAAAAAGUUAAUAAAAUAAAAUGAUCUGUAUGAUACCUGCAAUUGAAAAGCCGAAAAGAUUAUACUGUCAAGUCCAGUAAAUGACAUUUUUAGAGAUGCUUUUGUAGACAAGCAUAUGGAAUAUGUGAUUGUAUUUAUUUUCUGCAACUAAAAAAGGAAUAAAAACUUGUGUUUGUGUGUUUUUCUAAAACUUUGUGUUUUGGCAAUCGUUUUAUAACUAAAAUAAAAUGAAAGCUAAAUCUACACGCUGUGAAUGUUGAAA